GGAUCUGGCAGCCACUCAGCCCUUCGAGCUGUAGGGGAGGCGCUGCGCCCCCGGCCCCAGCCGAUCGGGGGCUCCUGGCGCUAGCCUCCCUCCAGAGCGCCGCAGGAGUCCCUCCUGCCGUCUGACUUGAGUCCCUGCUGCUGCAGUGCACGCCCCUUCGGCAGCCAGGGUGGGGCCCAGACCCAACCUGGCCCCUCCUGCCCCCACCCCGCCUUUGGGUCGCUGGUGAGUAGGGAGCUUUGAGGUAGGGGUGGGGGCGUCAGAGGCUGAAGAAAGAGGCACCUGGAGGAGAACACAGGCUUCUCCAGACUGGACCCUAACAGCAGAGAGAGGAGCGUGGUGGGUGGGCCACCACCACCAUUUCAGAGACCCCCAGGCUGUGGUGAGGGUCUGAGAGCUGGUACCACGGAGCCUGGGCAACCUCCUCCGCCCACCCAUGCCCACCCCGCAUGAGGCUGAGAAGCAGAUCACAGGGCCAGAGGAGGCGGACCGGCCCCCUUCAAUGUCCAGUCAUGAUACAGCCUCUCCAGCGGCCCCCAGCCGCAACCCCUGCUGCCUGUGCUGGUGCUGCUGCUGUAGCUGCUCCUGGAACCAAGAGCGGCGGCGCGCGUGGCAGGCCUCCCGGGAGAGCAAGCUGCAGCCCCUCCCCAGCUGUGAAGUAUGUGCCACGCCAAGUCCUGAGGAGGUGCAGAGCUGGGCGCAGUCUUUUGACAAGCUGAUGCACAGCCCAGCGGGACGCAGCGUGUUCCGGGCGUUCCUGCGGACAGAGUACAGCGAGGAGAACAUGCUCUUCUGGUUGGCCUGCGAGGAGCUGAAGGCCGAGGCCAACCAGCAUGUGGUAGACGAGAAGGCGAGGCUCAUCUACGAGGACUACGUAUCCAUCCUGUCCCCCAAGGAGGUGAGCCUGGACUCCCGUGUGCGGGAGGGCAUCAACAAGAAGAUGCAGGAGCCGUCCGCACACACGUUCGACGACGCGCAGCUGCAGAUCUACACGCUCAUGCACCGGGACUCCUACCCCCGCUUCCUCAGCUCUCCCACCUACCGUGCCCUGCUGCUGCAGGGGCCAUCACAGUCCUCCUCCGAGGCCUAGGCCGCCCCCAGCAGCACAGACCCCGCCGCCUCCUACGGCCGACUCUGGGUUCCCUUCAGGUGUUGUUGUCGGCAGGGCUGUCAGGGCACAUGCCUGGCCGGCUGGGGUCCCCACCCGCGGAGACGGUCCUAGACCCAGUGGGGAGUGCUGUGUCUCCUGGGUCUGCCCACCCGUGGCCAAGCAGGAACUCCAGGUGCAGGGCGGGCCUCCAGGUGCAGGGCGGGCCAGAAGCCCCCUCAUCGGCCCGCAGCUGGCUGGCCCAGUGCUCCUGGCUGGGGGCUCUUGCGUGGUGAGAGUAGGGGUCCCCCCAGGAGCCAUGCUGGACCCAUGAGCCUCGCUGGGGCCUCCUCCCCAGGCAGCCAAUGGGCCCCAGACAAGCCUUUGGUGGGGAACAGAACCUCCGCAUCGUGUAGUUUUGUGACAUAAGGAGACCUCCUACUUGAGCUGUCUGUACCCCAGAAUCAAACACAGAACCUCAGAACCAGAUUUAGGACCUCAGAAUCCUGCACUCAAGGUGGCAGGACCCAAUUUCUGUUUUAUAUGUUCAUGAACUUUAAACCUGGAAACAUGUCCUUACUAGGUGUUUUAUCAAAAAAAAGUUUUCAUAUUUAUCUCUAUCCCUAACCCCCCAAAAAUAGGAUGUCUUAUUAUUGAAGAUAUUUUUAAAGCAAA